GUCUUCUGCCCGGCCCCUUCGCCCACGUGAAGAACGCCAGGGAGCUGUGAGGCAGUGCUGUGUGGUUCCUGCCGUCCGGACUCUUUUUCCUCUACUGAGAUUCAUCUGUGUGAAAUAUGAGUUGGCGAGGAAGAUCGACCUAUUAUUGGCCUAGACCAAGACCCUAUGUACAGCCUCCUGAAAUGAUUGGGCCUAUGCGGCCCGAGCAGUUCAGUGAUGAAGUGGAACCAGCAACACCUGAAGAAGGGGAACCAGCAACUCAACGUCAGGAUCCUGCAGCUGCUCAGGAGGGAGAGGAUGAGGGAGCAUCUGCAGGUCAAGGGCCGAAGCCUGAAGCUGAUAGCCAGGAACAGGGUCACCCACAGACUGGGUGUGAGUGUGAAGAUGGUCCUGAUGGGCAGGAGAUGGACCCGCCAAAUCCAGAGGAGGUGAAAACGCCUGAAGAAGGUGAAAAGCAAUCACAGUGUUAAAAGAAGACACGUUGAAAUGAUGCAGGCUGCUCCUAUGUUGGAAAUUUGUUCAUUAAAAUUCUCCCAAUAAAGCUUUACAGCCUUCUGCAAA